AGAAGCCGCGGCUCCAGCUCGCCUGGCGGAAUUGCACGCGGCGGCGGGAGCUGGAAUAGCAGAAGGAACCACCUCGUGGAGUCGGGCCGGAGCCCUGCAGUGGCUCAGACGGUUGCAGGGACCGCCAGGUCGGUGCUGGCCGAGGGCCGGGAGGGCGGAGCUGGGCUGUGGGCAACAGGGUCCCGGCUCUCGCCUCGAGGCCUUGGGGCAGCUCGGGAAGCUGGGGAGCACGGCUUUCGGGGGGACAGCUCCCCAAGGCUGCCUGGGCACCGGAUGGGGACUGAGAGGCGGUAAAGGGGACACUCCCGGGUGCGCUCUCCGUGGUGCUGAAAGGACAGCUCCUUGCGAGGGGCCGCGAGCAGGCAGCUAGCUGCGAACUAAGAGGAAGCGUGGGCCCUAGCCGGAGACUCCGGGCAGAGCCCGAACGGCCGGGGUCCCGGAGCCAGGACCGCCCCGGCUGCGGCGGAGACUCAAGUCUGAACCCAGAGAACAACUUUGAGCUCGCGGGAGUGGGGGACGUCGAUCUAAGCUACUUCUGGCUGUGCUUAACCCGAAGCCCGCCGGAGCACGCUUCGCCCCGGAGGAGGGAGUCGCCCCCAGGGGUACAGUGCGCACUCCCGGAGUUGUCACAUCUUCCCAAGCCAGGCCAGCCAGGAGCGCUGCAUGCAAAUUCUGCCGUGGGCUAAGGCACGCUAACCAGAGCCGGCGGCAUGGACUUCGUCAUGAAGCAGGCCCUUGGAGGGGCCACAAAGGACAUGGGGAAGAUGCUGGGGGGAGAGGAGGAGAAGGACCCCGACGCGCAGAAAAAGGAGGAGGAGCGGCAGGAGGCGCUGCGGCAGCAGGAGGAGGAGCGUAAGGCCAAGCACGCGCGCAUGGAGGCGGAGCGGGAGAAGGUCCGGCAGCAGAUCCGAGAUAAGUAUGGGCUGAAGAAGAAGGAGGAGAAGGAAGCAGAGGAGAAAGCAGCCCUGGAGCAGCCCUGCGAGGGGAGCCUGACCCGGCCCAAGAAGGCCAUCCCUGCGGGCUGCGGGGACGAGGAGGAGGAGGAAGAGGAGAGCAUCCUGGACACGGUGCUCAAAUACCUGCCCGGGCCGCUGCAGGACAUGUUCAAGAAGUAACCAGGCCUCCUGCCCCAGCCUACUCCACCUGUUACUACUUCUUUUUGGUUCUUUCUUUUCUUUUUAUUAGGUUAAGUCUCAAUUCUGAAGGGGAAAACCUCAGUUGGCCUCUGCCCCUCUUCCCUGGCCAGGGGCUUCUCCCCCUCAGCUCUCCCUCACACCUCCCUUCAUCCCAGGGUAUCCACCUGCACCCCACUCCCAAGUAGCUUGAAAAAGGGAGGACAGUCUUUCCCCAGCAGGGGUCAGGGGGGCCCCUCAGGAAGCCUAAGGUCGUGCUAGUGUGGUGACCCCCAUACAUUCCUCCCUGCUCCCCACUGCCAGGAGGACCACUGUCCCCAGCCAGCCAAAGUAAUGACACAUUCCAGCCCUGCCCAGCAUGCUGACCUUUGGCCUCUAACCCUCAGUGGGCCCCCAGGUCAGGGCAGGGGCACUGAGUGGCCUGGCUCUGAGGAAGGGAGUCAGGGGAAGCCUGUCCCGGGAAGGCCCAGGCUGAGAGGCCCUGGCUCUGGCCAGGCUGGGAUCUGGGUGGGAGGCUGGGGCUCUUCUUCUUCCAUCUCCUUGGUGACACCCAGCCCAGGGGCACCCCCUUCCCCAGCCCCCACCUGGAGAGACAUGGCCCCUGCCAAGCUGGUCCCUUCAAAUGGAUCCUUUGUGGACUUUAGCUCAUUUGUGGAGGAACCCCAGGUAGGGACGCCCCUUGUUCCUCACCCCCACCCCACUUAGGUCCUGGGCCCCCACUGCCAGGCUGGGCCCAGCUUGCUCAGUCAAGGGGCUGCCAGGCCCCCAGAAAACACUUGGAGCCAUCGGGUAGCGAUGGUCUAUGCCAUGGGGAACACCUCCAUUGGUGUGGCCAAGCUGCCCCCAUUCCUAUCCACCCCUCUCCCCACCCCGUCCUGUCCAUGCGCUUCCAGGGCCCCACGGUCCCCAGGAGGACGCUUCCUGGCCAAAGCCCCAAGCCUUUGGUGAGAAGCCAAUUCCCACUUGACAGAAGGCGUCCAUCCAUUCAUCUCAUUGGCCAAGGACAAACUCUCCUCUGGGACGUCUGGGACUGGCAUUUGUCCCCCACUCAAAUUAUCAAAGCUUUCUGCUCAGUCAGUUGUGUGGGGAUGGUGAGGGAAGAGGGGUCACAUGAGGGAGGAAACUGUAUCCAUGCAUGCAUGAUAAUGCGUGGCAGAGACUGCAACAGGGAUUGUGUGUUCAGAGAUCAUAUGCAUAUGUGUAGGGCUGGAGCGUGUGUGUGUCUUGAGAUUGUGUGUGUUGCAGUCAUCAUAUCUAUGUGUUACAGAUUGUGUAUGUUAGCCUUGUGUAUGUGUGCUUGAUUGAGGUGGUGUAUUUGGGUUGAAAUUGUGUCAUAUGUGUGUGCUAUCCAUCUCGUGUUUAGAGGCUGUAUAUGUUAGCUUGUGUAAGAAUGUGUUUUCAAAACAGUGUGUGUAUUGGGAGUGAUGGGUAUGUGUUAGGUAUGUGAUGGGUUGUAGAAGCGUGUGUUUGAGAGAAUUCAGAGACAUUUGAAGGCUGCUGUGUGCAUGUUUGGGGGUCUGAAAAGACAGUUGUGUGCAUGGAUGUGUGCGUGGGGAGAAAGAACGUGGGUAAGAUGUCCCUUCCCAGCCCUGAGACCACUGGUCACAGUUGGCCACCUCCAACGGGAGACCUUGUCCUUGGCCUAGAGUCCUCCCACCCUUGGGGGGCUCCUGCCUGAGGUCCUCAGAAUCCCACUGCAAUGGACCCAGGCAGCGCCCCAGGAAGCCAUGCUGGGCCCCCGCCAGGGCCUAUCCCAAAAGCAGGGGCCAGGGAGGGGGCGACUUGCCUGCCCCUGAAGCCCUUGUUCCCAUUGGCCCCAGUUUGCAUUCUGCAGGUUUUCCAUUUUAGUGGGUUCUGCUUUUAUUUCAGAGACAGACAUGUGUCUUCUCUGUCCGUUUCCAAUAGGUAAAGCCAUAUCAGUUAGACUGCAAUACUUUAAACACGAGACAAAACAAUCCAUAUGUUUAGGGAACCAGAAAAGUCCCCUGGUCUGUCCCUUCUUUGGGGAGCAGGGCCUCGACAGCUCCAGCUCCCUUGACCUACCUUCCUCCCCGCACCCCGCCCCCACCUUGUGCCCCUGUGUCCAGCCCCCCAGGGGGCCUGUGUCUGUGUCUGUGCCUGUGUCUGUGAUGGGGAGCCGCCUCGCACCCCUGUUGUCUGCUUGUCUCUUUGUGUCUGUUAUCCUGGGCAGGAUGGUCAUUCUCAAAAACCCUGGGGUCCUGGGCCAGAGACAGGCAGGGCCCAGUCCAGGGGCCCCAGGCCUCCCCAGUCCCAGUGUGCGAGCCCCACUUGGACACAAGUGUUCAGAGAGGUCCCCCUCUGCCACUUGACAGGGACCUUCAAACCUCGACAGUGAUGCAAGGACACAGAGAGUACCAGAUAGGUAGCAGAGACCAAGGCGCAGGGUGCUUCAGAUGAGCAAGAGAACCCAGUCGAACCAGAUACCCCAGGUGGGCCGGAGGGACCCCAGACCUUCAGAGGGCUGCCCUGGUGUUCUCCACAGUGCAGUCCCUCUGUAUUCCCAGAGUGGGAUCGGGGCUUUCAGCCCCACCCUGAUGCCUGCCCUCCAGGAUGGCUGGUUUAGUCUGGGUCCAUGUCCCAGACCCCUCUAUUCUGCUCCAGGACAGCAGGACUUCAGGUCUUCCUGGGGGUGGAUAUAGGAGAAAAUUUCUGCCUGGCACACACCUGGCUCCAACCACUGCCAAGUGAUCACUCUUAGGCCCAGGGGAACACAAUGACUAUCAUUACUGAUGCAGACCUGGCUGUGGAGAGCAGCUAAUGUGUGGCCCAGAGAGCCUGUCUGUGUGGAGCACGUAGUGCACAGAAUACGUGAGAGUUGCUCUGGCAGGGGCAGAAUCCUCACAGGAUCGCCUGGGAGGUGAGGUGUGUGUGACCCACUGGAUGGGAGGGCAAUGAGUGUGCACAUACAAAUGGGGCAGUGUGCAUGCAACACACUUAGGGGAGGAGUGGCCCCAGAAUUCAGCACGCACACAACACACAAGGGAGAGAACCCCCAGAUGAGAAAAUAGGAAGGAGCAAUCAUUUGUAGAUGGGUGAAAAAAGAAUGAGGUUCAAGGGAGCGUGCACCAGGUGAGGUGAGCGUGUGUGCUCUCAGGGAAGGGCCCAGGAUCCCAUGCCUGGGAGGAGCUGCCAGAGAGAAGCAAAAAGGCGGCUGUGGAUCGCCCUGGGCUGGGCACCAGUGACAGGUCAGGAUCUCCAAACAUGGACGUCCUCCCCUCCAAAUCCAGAAGCUCCCAGAAGGUGUCCUUAACUGCAAAGCUGUGCAGGGUACUCCUCCAGAUGGAAUCAGGAAGUCGAGACACCAUCCCAGGUGUGUGUAAGAGAGAGAGAGAGAACAGGGAGGAUACAGAAGUAUUGCAGCCCAGAUCCCCUAUCAGGGGGACAGCUGGUGGGCAAAGCAGCCACCCCACAGCCUUGUGGCUAGAGUACAGUGGGGUAGACCCUCCAGCCCCAAUAGCCCUAGUACCCAGCUGGCAGGGUUGCCCACCCCUGCUGUCCACCUGCUCCAUCCUCUAGGGUUCCACAGGCCCCUGACCGCACAGGGAGGCUGGGGCCAGCCUGGUCUCCCAGGCCUGAGGACAUGCCUCCCACCAAAUGUCCCCUGCUCCAGUCCCACUCCUGUCACCCCACGCUCUGCACUGGGGAGAAAACGGGAGGUGCUCGUGCUGGCCCUGGGUGGGAGCGGGGAGUCCUGGUGAGACCCCGGUGAGAUGGACCAUCCUGCCCCCGUGGGGGAUCCCCUUUCCCACAUCCGUGCUGUGUCAUUGUUGCUCUGCUUCCUUUCAAUGUGUCAGUGCCUGGGGGGAGGGGAGGAGCACCCCCUCAGCCCCCCUGAACCUGACCAAAAGCCAUGGCUGUUGCUCCCCCCUUUGUAUGAUGCAAAUGCUGAAAUGUACAAAAUCAACCAUGACAACAAAGAAAAAGACCUUGUACAGCA